ACCACGCGUUCUCCCGCCCCGCGGAAGCCCAGGAGGCAGCGCAUUGGGCAUUCUGCGCCCAUGACUGCCGGGCAGGCUGAGGCGCGGGGCAGCCGCGGGAGGCUGCUGGCGGGGAUGGCGGUCCCGGGUGGUCCAUGCCUUUCUUCCCUCCCAGUUGCGGGUUCCGCUGGCGGCGGUGGCGCUGACAAGCCCGCGCCGGGGGGGCGGGGGAGUCCCUGCUCACACAGACUGCGCCCCCACGGAGUGAGGCCGCUUCCUAGACCUCGCCUAGUCGUCUUUCCUCUCCCUGCCCUGGGGGGGUUGCGGGGGUCAGUGCAAACUCCUGCGUCCAGGGCACUGGUGAGCUCCCGACUUCCGGCAGCCAGGGGGCUGAGGUCCCGAAGGAGGCUCCGAGGGGAGAGUCCUGCGUGUGCAAAACCUGGGAGGGGAGCCGAAGCCCAGAUGCUUCUGGGACUGAGCGCUCUCGAUGUGGAGCUGGAGUAGAGGGGAUGUGUGCGGCUGCAGUAGCAGGCGAGGGAGUGGGCUUUAUCUCGAGGGCGUCGGGAGACAUAGAAGUUUUGAACAGAAUCAGGACAUCCUCUGAGUUGGGACUUUAAAACGGUUCCACCGUUUGUUGCGUGGAGAACAGACAUGCAGGGGUGUCGGCAUGAAGGGAAGAACCGACUGCCACAGUCUGGGCAGCAGUGGAGGUGGGCGACCAGGUGAAUUCUGGUGGAUCUGCGGAUGCAUCAGGUGUGGGCUGUUUGAAGAACUAAGUACCCCAUGUUGUUCAGCCUGAGCGCCUGGAAGAAGAGAGCUGCUGUAGAUAGAAAGGAGAAUUGAAAGGAAAGCAGGUUUCCUUCAGGGGAAAGAUCAAGAGUCUGGGAUGUCCCAGGUUGGUCAUGUCACUGGACCUGACGUUGUUGGUGUCCUGGGCUGAGGACAGGGCCUAUAAACUGGACUGAAGAAGGCGAUGAGCAGUCAGGCGUGCGGAGUUACAGCUUGAGGGUUCUUGGGGCUGCACCCCUAUGACGACUGGUGGGGAUCAUCCAGUCCCUCAGGCUGGAUGAGCAGCCUGGAAAUGUCAGGACCUGAUGACCUUCGAGGAUGUGGCCGUGUACUUCUCCCAGGAGGAGUGGGGGCUCCUGGACACAGCGCAGAGGGCCCUGUACCGCCACGUGAUGCUGGAAAACUUCACACUUGUGACCUCACUUGGACUCUCUACCUCCCGACCUCGUGUGGUCAUUCAACUUGAGCGUGGCGAGGAGCCCUGGGUUCCCAGUGGAAAGGACAUGACCCUGGCCAGGAACACCUACGGGAGGCUCAACUCUGGUUCCUGGAGUUUGACAGAGGAUAGAGAUGUUUCUGGAGAAUGGCCACGAGCUUUCCCAGAUACCCCACCUGGGAUGACUACUAGCGUCUUCCCAGUUGCCGAUGCCUGCCACAGUGUAAAAAGCCUGCAGCGACAACCGGGUGCCUCCCCAUCUCAGGAGAGAAAACCCACGGGGGUGUCGGUGAUCUACUGGGAGAGGCUCCUGCUAGGCUCGCGCAGUGACCAGGCCAGCAUCAGCCUGCGACUGACCUCCCCACUCAGGCCCCCCAAGAGCAGCCGGCCCAGGGAAAAGACCUUCACAGAGUACCGGGUGCCUGGGAGGCAGCCCAGGACGCCUGAGCGGCAGAAGCCAUGUGCACAGGAGGUCCCUGGGAGAGCCUUCGGGAAUGCCUCGGACCUGAAGGCCGCCAGUGGUGGCAGGGAUCGCAGAAUGGGCGCAGCUUGGCAGGAGCCUCAUAGACUCCUCGGUGGCCAGGAGCCCUCGACCUGGGACGAGCUGGGCGAGGCUCUUCACGCUGGGGAGAAGUCCUUCGAAUGCAGGGCGUGCAGCAAAGUGUUCGUGAAGAGCUCCGACCUCCUCAAGCACCUACGCACCCACACCGGGGAGCGGCCCUACGAGUGCACCCAGUGCGGCAAGGCCUUCAGCCAGACGUCGCACUUGACGCAGCACCAGCGCAUCCACAGCGGCGAGACGCCCUACGCGUGCCCCGUGUGCGGCAAGGCCUUCCGGCAUAGCUCCUCGCUGGUGCGGCACCAGCGCAUCCACACGGCCGAGAAGUCCUUCCGCUGCUCCGAGUGCGGCAAGGCCUUCAGCCACGGCUCCAACCUCAGCCAGCACCGCAAGAUCCACGCGGGUGGGCGUCCUUAUGCUUGCGCACAGUGUGGCCGCCGCUUCUGCCGCAACUCGCACCUGAUCCAGCACGAGCGUACGCACACAGGCGAGAAGCCCUUCGUAUGCGCGCUCUGCGGUGCUGCCUUCAGCCAGGGCUCCUCGCUCUUUUUGCACCAGCGCGUGCACACAGGCGAGAAGCCCUUCGCCUGCGCCCAGUGCGGCCGCUCCUUUAGCCGCAGCUCCAACCUCACCCAGCACCAGCUCCUGCACACGGGCGAGCGGCCCUUCCGCUGCGUGGACUGUGGCAAGGGUUUCGCCAAGGGCGCCGUGCUGCUCAGCCACCGGCGCAUUCACACGGGCGAGAAGCCCUUCGUGUGCACGCAGUGUGGCCGCGCCUUCCGUGAGCGCCCUGCCCUCUUGCACCACCAGAGGAUCCACACCACAGAGAAGACCAAUGCCGCAGCACCAGACUGCACCCCGGGGCCAGGUUUCCUUCAGGGACAUCAUCGGAAGGUGCGCCGGGGAGGGAAGCCAAGCCCAGUCCUGAAGCCAGCGAAGGUCUGAGGUCACAGGUCGCAGCCCAACCCUUUCUUGGCCUUCUGUGAAUCCCUUCCACAGCUAAAGGGUCCGAGUGCUCUUCAGAUCCACGAUGGGGAAAAGCUCUGUGCCUGAGAGUCAGGGACGAGGGAGACCCUUUGGCUGUGGUUCCAUUUGCAGGUGGGGACAGGAUUUGCCAGUUUAGUCAUAGCUCACACCUCCAUCCUCAAAGAGGUAACACUGCAGAAACAUCAGAGGGAGGACAUGUCAGCUGGAACUCUGGUGGGGCUGAGGCUGUAGUUGGGGCCAUAGGACGCCGACAAAGGCAGCGCUGCAUGGUGGUGCUACUUCAUGUGUUAUGAGAGUGGAUGCUGAGGUGAGGGGGAUGCGGACAUGGGGUAGGAUGACCUAGAGAAACUUAUGAUGUCUGCACACAAACUGGCCGCUAGACGGACGCUGAGGACAUUUUCCCCCUGAGGCCUCUAUUCAAGGCUUCCUGGGGGCCAUCUCAGCAAACAGGAGACUACAGGGGACUGGGGAUCAGGGUGUGGCCUGUGAGUGUCAGCCUCCUCCUCGGAAAAAGAAAAGCUUUGGGUCAACUCAGCAUCAUGUUUGCAGAUGCUGACAGACGGGAUCCUAAUGAGAGUCAAUGUGUGCUCACUGCCAGCUCCUGGGCUGUGCUCUGGUCAGCCAGGUGUGAGGGCCUGGCCUGGGGUCACACAGCUGACUCAGGAGAGGAAUGCCCAUGGUUCUCAGCAUUGGAAGGACAAACCUAGGAUGAUGGCUUUCCAGUGGCACUCGUUCAGGUUUUCGUCCAAGUCUCAGCUUGGCCAAGGCCUGUCGCUCACUCAUUUACAAAAGUCGAUGUGAGGAGGAGCCUUUACACCUGUGGAGACAGUGAUAGCUUUGGAGCAGAUAAGGUGGAGCUGCUCAUUUUUGCUGGAUUUGGUGGCCGAUCCCCGCCCCCACCCCCACCCCCUCCAUCUCACCUUUCCCUUGUUAUGCCUCCUCAAUUGGAGGCUGGACAGAGAGCUGAAUAGGAAGGACUUGCCAUUACCUAAGGCCAUGUGUGACAGCCUCCUGAGGACCUCCCCAACCCAGUGUGAUGGGCCUGCAUGGCAGAGACAAAAGGGUAGACUGGGGGUCAUUUGCUUCCUGUGGCCUUAAGCCUACUAGGCCCCAUCCUUACCUGAGACCUCACCUCCAAGAAAUUAAUGGUCUUUUCAAUGGAGAAAAAAAAAGACUAGUAUUUGCAACUUCAAAUAGAUGUAGUUUCCUUUA